GUAGUACGAAUCCGUCAGGCCGGAACCAUGGCAGUGACCAAGGAGCUCUUACAGAUGGACCUGUACGCGCUGCUAGGCAUUGAGGAGAAGGCAGCGGACAAAGAGGUAAAGAAGGCGUAUAGGCAGAAGGCCCUCUCCUGCCACCCAGACAAAAAUCCAGAUAAUCCCAGAGCAGCUGAACUCUUCCACCAGCUUUCUCAGGCCUUGGAGGUGCUGACCGAUGCUGCAGCCAGGGCUGCAUAUGACAAGGUCAGGAAAGCCAAGAAGCAAGCAGCAGAGAGGACCCAGAAACUUGAUGAGAAAAGGAAGAAAGUGAAGCUUGACCUGGAGGCCCGGGAGCGGCAGGCCCAGGCCCAGGAGAGUGAGGAGGAAGAGGAGAGCCGGAGCACCAGGACACUAGAGCAAGAGAUCGAACGCCUGAGAGAAGAGGGUUCCCGGCAGCUGGAGGAACAGCAGAGGCUCAUCCGGGAGCAGAUACGCCAGGAGCGUGACCAGAGGUUGAGAGGAAAGGCAGAAAAUACUGAAGGCCAAGGAACCCCCAAACUAAAGCUAAAAUGGAAGUGCAAGAAGGAGGAUGAGUCAAAAGGUGGCUACUCCAAAGACGUCCUCCUACGGCUUUUGCAGAAGUAUGGUGAGGUUCUCAACCUGGUGCUUUCCAGUAAGAAGCCAGGCACUGCUGUGGUGGAGUUUGCAACCGUCAAGGCAGCGGAGCUGGCUGUCCAGAAUGAAGUUGGCCUGGUGGAUAACCCUCUGAAGAUUUCCUGGUUGGAGGGACAGCCCCAGGAUGCCGUGGGCCGCAGCCACUCAGGACUGUCAAAGGGCUCAGUGCUGUCAGAGAGGGACUACGAGAGCCUCGUCAUGAUGCGCAUGCGCCAGGCGGCCGAGCGGCAACAGCUGAUCGCACGGAUGCAGCAGGAAGACCAGGAGGGGCCGCCUACGUAGCCCCAGCUCCAGCCAUCCACCCCUCAGCCCUUUUCUUCAACGUCACCAAUAAAUUUUUUUUUUUUUUAAGAUUUUACCUCUAUCCCAUACAUAGGUAUAAGGUGCUGGGCUCUGCCGCAGAGCGCUCCACCCAGGCCUGGCGCCCCUCCCAGGAAGUGGGCAGACCCCCAGGGAAACGCUCCGCAGGGUGAGAGUCCCAGAGUCCGUGCACAAGCAGAGCACAGGCGCAGCCACUCAUCACAGCCCUUUAUUGGCUUGGGCUAGCUAUGCAGGAGCCACGCGCCAGGGCCGCUGGAGUGCCCAGCUCCGGCCCGGGGCAGCUGCCCGAGGAACAUGGCCUACACAAGGCCCUCGGCCCAGGCCCGAAGCAGGAGGGCAGCUGGGAGCACCAGGGCACCGGGCACUGCCCUCUCCCACUGCUUGACGCAGGGUUUCAGAGAAGGCCAUUCACUGCCCUUUGGGGCUGGGCCCAUGGCGGUGAUGAUUUGGGAAGAGAGGAGCAAGGCAGACGGUGAGGCAGGAGCUUGGAGGUCAGGGCCCACAGCAGCCCCUCCACAGGGGUGCCCCGUCUGCAAAUCAGCAUGAGAAGGUCACUCCUUGUGCAGACACCACACCAGCGUCUGGCCCACCCCCGUCAUGCUCAGCACACGGAAGCCCCUGCGUUCCAGCUUGUCCAGGACUAUGCGGGGAGGGUCAUCGACGUAGUAUUCAUAACUGCAAAGAGACAGGAUGGGGGGGGUGAGGAGGGGCACACAGCAAGCUCCUGGUACAAAGCUAGUGUCUGCAGCAGGCAGCCUGGCCACUCUUGUAGUGACUCACACUUGCUGGCUGCUUGCUGGGCGCUGGGGUAAGUGCACGCCCCCUGCCUCCUCCCCUUCUAGGUACUUCACGAGCUAUCUCAUUUAUUCUUCCCAACAAGCUAGUGAAGGUGCCACUGUUGUGGCCAUUGAUAGAUGAGAAAACAGAGGGGUUAAUCAGGUUCCCCAGCGUCCCAGAUGGUAGACCAUGUUAGUCUGACCACAGCCCUGCUGCCGCCCUCCCUGGGCUUGCUCCCCACCCAGGCUUCCAGGUAGGAGGAGGCUGAGGCUGCAGUGAGCCAUGAUUGCACCACCGCACUCCAGCCUGGGCGACAGAGACUCCAUUUCAAAAAAAAAUAAGCCUCCAGGCCCCUCACUGCCCUGGCUGUCCUGCAGUUCUGUAGCAACAAGGCUGAGCCCCAGUAGCUCCUGGCUCUGUGCGCCACUCCCUAGCAUGGAGAGUGCUGGUAGUCCUUCUGUCAGGUUUAAUUGAUGCUGAAAGACCAUGAAGCAGACAAAGGGCUCAAGCCCCAAGCUGGGCAUGGAGAGGCAAGUGCCUCAUGGCAAAGGGAGGGGGCUGGCUUCUGUCCCCGAGCCUUGACCCAGGGGCUGGGAUCAGCCCUCCUCUUUCCCCGAUUUGAACUGGCACUCACUCUGACAACUCUUUUCAGAGAGCCUGUGUAGCUUGGGUUCUCCCUGCCUCCAGGGGUGAGAGGAGGAAUGGAAGCAGUAGUCACAGUUUAGACAUGGAGGCAUUAGGAAGAAUGCCAAGGGAAAUGGCUAGGUCCCCAGGCAGCAGCCACCCUGGAGGUAGGACGCAGGCUCCCUGCUCCCUGCUUCUAGGGCUUAGCUUUGCGACUCAUGCAGAUCCUCACGACAAAAACCUUUCUCUCUGUGCCUGUCUGUCCUUGAUGGGGUCCAGCUUAGGAGAGGGCAGGGCAAGGAACAGUCUGCUAGUGGAGUCCUAGACCCAGGGAACGGACUCUGUUUCUGCGGUUCCAGUAAGGAUGUGGAAAGCUUUCAGAGCAAGCCUCGUGGGGGAGAGGGGGGAUGUUGGAGAGGCUACAGAUGGGACCAACUCCUCCGGAGAACAGAGCCCCAGGAUGCAGGCAGGGGGCUCUGAUGCUGGGCCCUGUCCCUGGGCUUGGAGGUUGUAUAAAGGGAGCAGAGGCAGGUCUAGGGGCUGGCAGGGAGAGGAUACUGAGGGAGGCUGCUACUUACAAGUUGUUUCCCAAGGCUCUUCUCUUUGAAGCCCCCAGAUGCUGCAUCAGCUCUGGAUCCGACUGUUCAUCGCCCACCAUAGUGGGGCCCACCUCCUGCAAGGUAAGCCACAGUGGCUGCUUGGCUGGCUGCCAGGAGGAGGUGGAAGGUCUUGCCUGUCCUUCCUCCCCUGCCUGCUAGCCCUGAGUAAGGUUCAGGUAAAGGCUACAGAGAGUAGCAAGGAUUCUUAGGGGCUGAGCACAAGCUGUGAAGGGGUGGAGCCCAUCAAUGAUCAGGAGGAGCAAUGUAGGCGCCCUCCCUAGUGCCUUAAAGCUCAGCUUUAGCCAGGCAAAGUAUCACGAGCCUAUAGUUCCAGCUACUGAGGCUGAGGUGGGAGGAUCGCUUGAGGUGGGAGGAGUUUGAGGCUGCAGUGAGCCAUGAUUGCACCACUGCACUCCAGCCUGGGUGACAGAGUGAGACUCCAUUUCAAAAAAACAAAACAAAAUAAACAUGUAAAUGAAAGAAGCCAGACUCAGAUCACAUUACCACAGAAAGGUAAUUAGUGGUUAUCUAGGGCUGAGGGACUUGGGGGAAAUCAAGAGUGUCUGCCAGUGGGUACAGGGUUUCCUUUUGGGGUAUUAGAAAUGUUCUAAAACUGAUUAUGGUGAUGGUUGCACAACUCUGAGUACACUAAAGAAACAACAACACUGAAUUGUACACUUUAAAUCAAAGAAUUUAUGGUAUGCACAUUACAUAUCAAUAAAGCCAUAUCUUUUAAGAAA